GCCAUUAACAAAGAUGGUGCUUAUGGGGCAGGUUCCCUAACAGUCAGGAUUCCGGUUGCAGUUUUUCUCCCCCGCCCCAAAGAUACGUGGUUGCAGACGGAGAAAUGGAGGCCAGAGACAAACAAGUACUCCGCUCACUUCGCCUGGAGCUGGGUGCAGAGGUAUUGGUGGAGGGACUGGUUCUUCAGUACCUCUACCAGGAAGGAAUCUUGACGGAAAACCAUAUUCAAGAAAUCAAUGCUCAAACCACAGGCCUCCGGAAAACAAUGCUCCUGCUGGAUAUCCUACCUUCCAGGGGCCCUAAAGCAUUUGAUACAUUCCUAGAUUCCCUACAGGAGUUUCCCUGGGUCAGGGAGAAGCUGAAGAAGGCAAGGGAAGAGGCCAUGACCGACCUGCCUGCAGGUGACUACUGAGCUUGGUGGCAGAAUUGAGAAUAAAGACUCCCUGACUUCAGACCAGUGUUCUCUCUGUUCCAGUAGUGUUUUCAAUCUGGGACCAUAGAGCUGCUCAAAUUCAAGCAAAAUAGAAUCUUUUUUGUGUGUGUCUUUAUUUUGAAGAUCGUUUUUUUUUAAAGCCAUUUUCAAAAACAGUUUUUCAGUUGGGGUACAUUGACCUCUGAAAGUUCUAGGACACAGUCUCAGGAGCCCAUGAGAUUUAGUUCUCCUUCCCACCACUUCAAAAGAGGUCUGUGCGGUACUCUAGGUUCAGAAACUUGGCACCAUGAUAUUUUGCCAGUUUAUCUUAUUAACUGAAUGCUGUCUGUAGUGACUCUGCAGAAAACAGUGUUAUGUUCUUCUGUCAGACUUGUGCUGUUCAAUAUGGUUGCACGUAGCUAUGUGUGGCCAUUGAGCGUGAAAAUGUGACUCCUGUAAGUUGAUUAUAGACUACCAUGUAAUAUAGUCACCCCUCAGUGUCCGAGGGGUAUUGGUUCCAGGACCCCCUGCACAUACCAAAAUCCACAGAUGCUCAAGUUCCUCAUAUAAAAAUGGCAUCGUAUUUUUAUGUGAUCUACAUACAGCCUCCUGUAUACUUUAAAUCAUCUCUGGAUAAUUUAUAAUACCUAAUACAAUAUAAAUGCUUUGUAAAUAGUUGUUAUAUUGUUUGUUUGUUUUCUUAACGUUUUUUUUAAUGGUUGUAUUGUUAUUGUUUAUUUAAAAAAUAUUUUCAAUUCAAGGUUGGCUGAAUCUGCAUAUACAGAACCUGGGGAUACAGAGGGCUGACUAUAUCAUACACAUUAGAUUUCAAAGACUUAGUAUGAAAAAAUAAUGUAAAUAUCUCAUGAUUUAUUUUGAAUAUCUGUUGAAAUGAUAUUUUUGAUAUAUUGGGUUACAUAAAAUAUAUUAAAAUUAAUUUCAUCUGGCUUUUCCUUUUUAAAACGUGGCUACUAGACAAUUUAAAAUUAUAUAUGUGACUGGCAUUCAUUAGAACUUGACACCUCUCUCAGGAGGAAAGGUGGAAGGAACUGGUGGAUAUCACUGUGCAGAUGAGGUGAUAUGACAGCUGCCUUCAGCUCUUUGGAUGGCUCUCAUUCGUAAAAGAGAUUCUUUCUGUUCUGUGUUUCUCAAAAGGUCGAACGAAGACAUAGAAAAAGCAAGUUAAUGUAAGAUAGACCCUUCUAAAAUAGUUGUCCAAAGAAAAUAUAGGCUCCUUCUAGAGAUAAUGAAUUCCUUGUCACUAUACAUAAUUCAAGAAGAGGCUAAAUAGCUGCUUAAUGAGGUUGUUUAGAGGGAGAUCAGGUGGUUAAAAGUAAUGCCUUUCCAAUCCUGAGAAUUUGUGACUUGAUGAAAUUGGGCAAAGGGCUGAUUUUACAGCUACAUGAAAUAAAUGGAUUCCGUGGGCAGGAGAAGAAAGCAUUUUAUUUCACUCCCUGUGCUUUUCCUUUAAACUUUCACAUGAGUAUUUUCCAGUUGAGGAGCUUUUGCAUUCUUGGUUACAGAAAGAUGUUUGAUUGUCUAAUCCCAGGGAAUCUGGUGAACAGUGUAUCAGUUAGGAAUGUGCUUGGCAACAAGUAAACAAACAAACAAACCAAAGUGACAAUGGCAAAUAAGUAGAGAUUUAUUUUAAUCCUGUAACAAGAACUCUGGAGGUCAGCUGCUUCUGGCAUUGAUUCAUUGGCUCAAAGGCAUCAGAGCGAGUGUCUCUGCUAUUCUCUUGGCCUUCCUUUUCCUCGUAGUAGCAAGGCAGUCACAGCUACCAACAGCACAUCCGUAAGGCUGGAAGAGGCACGGAAGUUGCUCAGCCCCUACUGCGUCUGUCACUUUUUCUUGGGAAAAGAAGUAGUCUUUCCAGAAAUCCUCAACACAAUUCCUCUUCUGAUUCAUUGGGCAGAAUUGUCUCAUGGCCACUCCUUGGUACAAGGGAGGCUGCAAAGUGAAUGUUUGCUCUUCUAGACUCUACGAUUGAGACAAGACAGGAGGAGAAGGAGGUUGGGAAUGGCAUUUGUGUCAGCCAAAAAGAACAGGGUCUGCCGCAGAUAGUUUUAGGUGUGACUGAGGGCACCACUCCCAAGUCAAACAUCAAGUGCUUGGGAGUUGAGACAUCAUCCAAUGUCCUUUUUUUAUUAAAAAAAAAAUUCUUUCACUAAGUGGUUUUAGCUGCCAUUGAUGAUUGUAGCCUUGGAUGAGUUUUAUUAAACAAUUCUUUCUUUUUAGAGAAGAAAAAAUUGAGGACCCGAGAAGUUAACGCCUUUGAUUUCUAUUGAAAUUACUCAUAGGGUAAGAGUGAGAGUUCUUGCUUUGCCCUUUCCACCUUCCUGACUUCAUCAGCAAAGAAGAGAAUCUUGGUUUUAUUUUUCAUUAUCUGCAAAUGAUAUGUCCAUAACAGUAGUUAUUUGUCACAAAAAUACUUCACAAGAACAUUGGUAAACACAUACAAAUGUUAGCAGUUCUGAACAGGCAUUUAUUGUAGAGGAACCUGUUUAUGAUGAGAAAUAUGAAAGAAUUGAGACAGUGGGCCUCUACCAUAGAGGAGGGAAGAAACUAGUUGGGUGAAAUUUAGUGUUAGGAUGUUUUGUCAAAAAACUAUUUUUGGGAGGCUGAGGCAGGAGGAUGGUUUGAGCCCAGGAGUUCCAGACCAGCCUGGACAACAUGGCAAGAUUCCAUAUCUACAAAAAUAAAUAAAUAGAAAUUUAAAAAAAUUUUUUUCAUCUUUAGCAUUAAUGGCAAAUAUUUAGAGCUAUAUUUAAUGGAAGUAUAUGUGAAUUGGUGGUAUAAACAGAUUUUUCCAAACUCUUUUUACUUGUAAUUUCUGUGGCUGUAACAACUUUUACUAGCCUCUUAGGAGUUUCUUAAAUCCUUUUUCCCCAUUUUCUUUGGUCUAUGAUAAAGAAGUAAUCUGAAGUAGAAAAAAAUUAUUUAGGCUGGGCACAGUGGCUCAUGCCUGUAAUCCCAGCACUUUGAGAGGCUGAGGCGGGGGGAUCGCUUGAGGUCAGGAGUUCGAGAUUAGCUUGGCCAACAUGGUGAAAUACAAAAAUACAAAAAUUAGCCAGGCGUAGUGGCAGAUGCCUGUAAUCCAAGCUACUCGGGAGGCUGAGGCAUGAGAAUCGCUUGAAUCCAGGAGGCGGAGGUUGCAGUGAGCUGAGAUUGUGCCACUGCACUCUAGCCUGUGUGACAGAGCAAGACUCCACCUCAAAAAAAAAAAAAAGGAAAAAAAUUACUUAGAUGAGCUAAUUUUUGAAGAUGGUCUUAUAAAGUUUAUUUUUUAUUAAUACACUUUAUUUUUUAGAGCAGUUUUAGAUUCCCAGCAAUAUUGGGUGGAAAGUAUGAAGAAUUGCUAUAUACUCCCUUCCCCUGCAGAUGCACAGCUCCUCCCACUGUCUACAGUUCCCAGGAGAGGUGUGACAUUUGUUAUCAUUGAUGAACUUAUAUUGACACAUCGUUAUUACCCAAAGUCCAUAGUUUACCUUAGGGUUCAUUCUUGAUAUUGUACAUCCUAUGGGUUGGGACAAAUAUAUAACGACAUGUAUCCACAUUUAUGGAAUCAUACAGAGUAUUUUCACUGCCCUAAAAAUUCUCUGUGCUCUUGAUUGUUCAUCCCUCCUUCCACACAACCCCUAGAAACCACUGAUUGUUUUACUAUCGCCAUAGUUUUGCGUUUCUAGACUACUAUAUCGUUGGAAUCAUGUAGUGUGUGGCCUUUGCAGAUUGGCUUCUUUUACUUGGCAAUAUGCAUUGAAGUUCCCCCCAUGUUUUUUCAUGACUUAAUAGCUCGUUUCCUUUUAGUGCUGAAUAAUAUCCCAUUGUCUGGAUAUCACCGUUUAUUUAUCCAUUCACCUACUGAAGGAUAUCUUGAAUGCUCCAAGUUUUGGCAAUUAUGAAUAAAGCUGCUUAUAAACAUCUAUGUGCAGGUUCCUGUGUGGACAUGCAUUUUCAGUUCAUUUAGGUAAAUAUCAAGAAGCAUGACUGCUGGAUCAUAUUUUAAGAAUAUGUUUAGUUUUGUGAAGAAUUACCAAACUGUCUUCCAAAGUGGCUAUACCAUUUUGUGUUCCUACCAGCAAUAAAUGAGAGUUCCUGUUGCAUCACACUAUACCAGCAUUUGGUGUUGUCAGAGUUUUGGAUUGUGACCGUCUAAUGGGUGUAUAGUGGUAUCUCAUUGUGUUUUAAUUUGUGUUUCCUUAAUGAUAUAUGAUGUUGAACAUCUUUUCACAUACUUACUUGCCAUCUGUAUAUCUUCUUUGGUGAGAUAUCUGUACAGGUCUUUGGCCAUUUUUUAAAUCAAGUUGUUCAUUUUCUUGUUGAAUUUUAAGAGUUCUUUGUCUAUUUUUGGUAACAGCCCUUUAUCAUAUGUGUCCUCUGCAAAUAUUUUUUCUAGUCUAACUCAUCUUCUCAUUCUCUUGACAGUGCCUUUCACAGAGCACACUUUUUAAUUUUAAUGAAAUCUAGCUUAUCAAUUAUUUCUUUCAUGGAUUUCUGCCUUUGGUGUUAUACCUAAAAAGUCAUCACCAUACCCAUAAUAACCUAGAUUUUCUCCUAUGUUAUCUUCCAGGAAUUUUAAAGUUUUGUGUUUUACAUUUAGGUCUGUGAUCUAUUUUUAAUUUUUUUAGAGUUUCGCUCUGUUGCCUAGGCUGGAGUGCAGUGGCAUGAUCUUGGCUUACUACAACCUCCGCCUCCUGGGGUUUAAGCAAUUCUCCUGCCUCAGCCUCUCAAGUAGCUGGGACUACAGGCAUGCACCACCACAUCUGGGUAAUUUUUGUAUUUUUAGUAGAGAUGGGAUUUCACCAUGUUGGCCAGGCAGGUCUCAAACUCCUGACCUCAAGUGAUCCACCCACCUUGGGCUCCCCAAGUGUUAGGAUUACAGGUAUGAGCCGCCGCACCCUUCCUGUGAUCUAUUUUGAGUUAACUUUUAUGAAGGGUCUAACAUCUGUGCCUGGAUUCUUUUUGUUUUUUUGCACGUGGAUGUUCAGUUGUUCCAGCACCAUUUGUUGAACGGACUGUCUUUGCCCCAUUGUAUUGCUUUUGCUCCAUUGUCAAAGAUCACUUAACUUUGUUUAUGUGAGUUUAGUUUUGGGUUCUCUGUUCUAUUCCAUUCAUCUAUUUGUCUGUUCUUCUACCGAUAUCACACUCUCUUGAUGACUGUAGCUGUACAUUAAGCCGUAAAGUCAGGUAGUGGCAGUCCUUAAACUUUGUCCUUUAACAUUGAGUUGGCUGUUCUGGGUCUUUUGCCUCUAUAUAUAAACUUUAGAAUCAGUUUGCCAGUAUCCACAAAAUAGUGUGCUGGGAUUUUUGUUGGGAUUGCAUUGAAUCUAUGAAGUUGAGAAUAGCUGACAUUUUGACAGUGUUGAGUCCAUGAACAUGGGAUAUCUGUUUAUUCAAUUCUUCUUUGGUUUCUUUCACCAGUUUUGUGGUUUUCCUCAUAUAGAUCUUGUACGUAUUUUAUUAGAUUUAUACCUAAGCAUUUUGAUCUUUGGGGGGGUGCUAAUGUAAAUGGUAAUGUGUUUUUAAUUUUUAAUUUCACUUGGUCAUUGCUGGUAUAUGGGGAGGUAAUUGACUUUUGUAUAUUAAACUUUUAUUCUGAAUCUUCUUAUAAUUGCUUAUUAGUUCCAGGAAUUUCUUGUUUAUUCUUUUGGAAUUUUCUACAUAGACAAUCAUGUCAUCUGUGAAGAAGACAGUUUUGUGUCUUCCUUCUUAAUCUACAUACCUUUUGUUUCUUUUUCUUGUCUUAUUGCACCAGUUAUGACUUCCAAUUUGAUCUUGAAAAGCAGUGGUAAUAACGGACAUCCUUGCCUGGUUCCUGGUCUUAGUGGGAAAGUCUCAAUUUUCUCUCUUUUUUUUUUUUUGAGACACGGUCUGGCUCUGUCACCCAGGCUGGAGUGCAGUGGUGUGAACAUGGCUCACUGCAGCCUUGAUCUCAUGGGCUGAAGUAAUCCUGCCACUUCAGUCUUCCAAGUAGCUUGAAAUACAGAUGUGCACCACCAUGCCUGACUAAUUUUUGUAUUUUUUGUAGAGAUGGGGUUUUGUCAUGUUGCCCAGGCUGGUCUUGAACUCCUAGGCUCUAGCAAUCUUCUUGCCUCAGCCUCCCAAAGUGCUGGGAUUACAGGUGUGGGUCACUGUGCCUGGCUGACUUUCUCACUGUUAAGUAUGAUGUUAGCUGCAGGGUUUUUAAAAAUAUGUUUUUUAUCAAGUUGAGGAGAUUCCCUUCUAUUCCUAGUUUGAUGAAAGUUUUUAUUAUGAAUAGGUGGUGAGUUUUGUCAAAUGAUAUGAUCAUGUGAUUUUUCUAAUUAAGUCUGUUGAUGUGAUGGAUUAGAUUACAUUUAUUGAUUUUGUAUGUUGAACCAGCCUUGCAUAAUUGGGAUAAAUCCCACUUGGUCAUGGUGUAUAAUUCUUUUUAUACAUUUUUAGAUUUGAUUUGCUAAUACUUUUUUGAGGAUUUUUGCGUUUAUGUUCAAGAGAGACAUUGGUCCAUAGUUUUCUUUUCUUGUAAUGUCUUUGGUGUUGGUAUUAGGGUGAUGCUGACUUCAUAGAAUGAGUUAGGAAGUAUUUCCACUGCUUCUAGUUUCUGAAAGAUAUUGCAGAGAAUUGUUACAAUUUCUUCCUUAAAUGUUUGAUAGAAUUUAUCAGUGAACUCACCUGGGCUUGGUACUUUCUAUUUUAAAGGUUAUUAAAUAUUGAUUCAAAUGUUUAAUAGAUGCAGGCCAACUUAGAUUGUUUAUUUUUGUGUGUGAGUAUUGGCAGAUUGUGUUUUUCAAUGAAUUGUUCCUUUUCAGGUAUGUUAUCAAAUUUGUGGGCAUAAAGUUGUUUAUAAAACUUCUUUAUCCUUUUAAUGUUCAUGGGAUCUGUAAUGAUGUUCUCUUUUUCAUUUCUGAUAUUAGUAAUUUGUAUUCUGUCUCCUUUUUUCUUAGCCUGUCUAGAUGCUUACUGAUUUCAUCUAUCUUUUCAAAGAGCAAACAUUGCUUUAUUGAUUUUUUCCAUUGAUUUCUUGUGUUCUCUUUCGUUAAUUUCUGCUCUAAUUUUUAUACUUUUUUUUGCUUUUGCUUACUUUGGAUUUAAUUUGCUUUUCUUUUUCUAGUUUCUAAAGGGGAAAACUUGGGUUGUUGAUCUUAGGUCUUUCUUCUUUCCUAAUUUUUGCAUCCAAAUCCUAUGCAUUUCCCUUUGCUUUAGCUAGAAACUACAAAUUUUGAUAAGUUGUUUCCAUUUUUAUUUAGUUCAAAAUAUUUUUUUAAAUUAUCUUGAGAAUUCUCUUACCCCUAUGUUACUUAGAAGUGUAUUGUUUUAUCUCCAAGUACUUUGGAAUUUUCCAGCUAUGUUUUUGUUAUUAAUUUUUUAUUUAAGUCCAUUGUGAUCUGACAGCAGAUUUUAUAUGGUUUCUAUAUUUUUAAAUUUAUUAGAGUGUGUUUUAUGGCCUAAAAUGUGGUCUAUCAUGGUGAAUAGUCCACAUGAGCUUGAGAAAAAUGUGUAAUCUGCUGUUGUUUGAUGGAAUAGUCUAUAGAUGUCAUUUACAUACAAUUGAUUGAUGUUGAGUUUAUGUCCUUCCUGAUUUUUUGCCUGCUAGAUAUGCCUAUUUCUGAGGGAUGCUAAGCCUCCAAAUGUAAUAGUGGAUUCACCUCUUUUUUCUUACAGUUCUAUCAGUUUUACCUCAUGUAUUUUAAUGCUCUGUUGUUAGGCACAUACACACUAAUGAUUGUUACGUAUUCUUGGAAUAUUGACCCCUUUAUCAUUUUGUAACGCCUCUCUCUAUCUCUGAUAACCUUUCUUGCUCUGUAGUUUGCUAUGUCUGAAAUUACUGUAGCUACUCCCACUUGCUUUUGAUUAUUGUUAGUGUGGUAUAGCUUUCUCCAACCAUUUAAAUCUACAUAUGUCUUUAUAUUUAAAGUGGACUUUUUGUAGACCACAUAUGAUUGGGUUUUGUUUUUUGAUCUACCUUGACAAUUCCUGUUUUUCAAUUAGUGUGUUUAGACCAUUGGCAUUUGAGGUGAUUGUUAGUUGGGUAUAUAGUUGGAUACCUACCAUAUUUGUUAUUGUGUUUUAUUUGUUGCCCUUGUUUUUUGUUUCUAUUUUUAUCUUCCACACUUUUUUGCCUUUUAUGGUUUAUUAUUUAGUAUUAAAUCAUUUUACAUUAUUCCAUUUUCUCUUUUGUAACAUAUAAAGUAUACUUGUUUUUAAAAAUUAUUUGUAGAAAUGAAGUCUCAACUGUGUUGCCCAGGCAGGUCUCAAACUCAUGGGCUCAAACAGUCUUCCCAUCUUGGCCUCCCAAAGUGCUGGGAUUAACAGAUGUGAGCCACCAUGCUCCUUUUUUUGUUUUUUUAAACUUUUUUAAAGUGGUUUCCCUAGAAGUUUGCUGUAUAUAUUUACAACUCAUCCAAGACCAAUUUCAAAUAACUCUGUACUAAUACAUGGGCAGUGUAUUUCAUUAUAAUAAUGAAAUAUUCCUAAUUUCUCCCUCCUGUCUUAUGCUGUCAUUCAUUUCACUUAUACGUUAGUGUAUAUAACUAUAUGUGUAUGCACAUACACAAACACACACACAUAUAUAUAUACACACACAGCCCUCCAUAUAUGUGGGCUUUGCCUCCAUGGAGUCAACCAACUGUGGAUCAGAAUAUUUGAAAAAUAAGGGAUAAUUGCAUCUGUACUGCACAUGUACAGAUGUUUUUCUCUUGUCAUUAUUUUCUAAACAAUACAGUAUAACAACUAUUUGCAUAGUAUUAGGUAUUAUAAGUAAUCUAGAGAUGAUUUAAAGUACAUAAGAUGAUGUAUGUAGAUUAAAAGCAAAUAAUGCAUCAUUUUAUAUAAGGGACUUGAGCAUUCAUGGAUUUUGGUAUCCACUGGGGGUGGGGCCCUGAAGCCAAUCUCCCAUGGAUAAUAAGGGACUACUGUACACAUAAGCAUACAUAACCAAAUACAUUGUUGCCAUUAUUAUUUUGAACAAACUUUGAUCUGUUAGAUCAAUUAAAAAAAUAAACAUUUUUGUUUUACCUCCACUUACUCCUUCUUGAUGCUCUUGUUUUCUUUAUGUAGAUCUUAUUUCUGACCUAACAUUAUUUUCCUUCUCUCAAAAGAACUUCUUUUAACAUUUCUUGUAAGGCAGGUCUACUGCCAACAAACUCUGUCAAUUUUUGUUAGUCUGAGAAAGUCGUUAUUUCUCCAUCAGUUUUGAAGGAUAGUUUCACAAGGUACAAGAAUUCUAAGUUGGUGGGUUUUUUCUUUUCCUCUCCACACUAAAUAGUUCACUCCACUUUGUUCUUGAUUAUGUGAUUUCUGAGAAGGCAGAUAUAAUUUUUAUCUUUGUUUCUCUAUAGCCAAUUUACUUUUUUUCUCUGAUUUCUUUCAGGAAUUUUUCUUUAUCUUUUACUUUUUGUAGUUUGAAACGAUAGCCUAGGUAUAGUUUUUGUUGGCAUUUAUGCUGCUUGGUAUUCUCUAAGCUUCCUGGAUCUGUGGUUUGGUGUCUGGCAUUAAUUUGGGGGCAAUUCUCAGCCUAUAUUGUUUCGUAUAUUUUUUCUGUUUCUUUCUUUUUCUCCAUCUAGUAUUUCCACUAUACCUAUGUUAAACCUUGUAUACUUGUCCCACAGUUCUUGGAUAUUCUGUUUUUCAGUCUUUCUUCUCUUUGCUUAUCAGUUUUGGAGGUUUCUAUUGAUACAUUCUUAAGCUCAGAUAUUCUCUCCUUAGCUAUGUCCAGUCUACUAAUAAGCCUACCAAAGACGUUCUUCAUUUCUGUUACAGUGUUUUUGAUCCUUAACAUUUUUUUUUCUUAAGAUUUCUAUUUCUUUGGUUACAUUGCCUAUGUGUCCUUGCAUGCUGACUAUCUAUUAGAGCCCUUAACAAAUUAACCAUAGUUGUUUUAAAUUCCCUAUCUGAUAAUUCCAACAUCCUUGUCAUGUCUGUUUCUGAUGCUUGGUCUGUCUCUUCAAACUGUGUUGUUUUGCCUUUUAGUAUGCCUUGUAAUUUUUUCUUGAUAGCUGGGCAUGAAUAUGGGGUAAAGGGAUCACUCUUAAGUAGGCCUUUAGUAAUGUAGUGAUAGAAGUGUGGGAGGAGAGGAAGUGAAACCAUCUUUGCAAAAAUUAUGACCAUGAGAAAAAUUUUGGCAUAGGAAAGUUAUGGCAGUGAAAGAAAUCUAACCUAACUGACUCCAUGUUGCUUCUCACCUCCAAGCUGUUCCUAUUCAUUCCUGGGCAUAGGCCAAACAAAAUAUAGGAGGAAUUUACUUUAUAGUUUAAUUUUGAAGCAAAGAUGAUAACAGCCCCUUCCUGAGACAAACCCCCUCUUUGCUUAGGGAUUAGACCAUCUUUGUAAAACUGAAACGUUAGCCACAAGAUUAGAAAUUCUGGCUCAGGAGUCAUGUAGCCAGAGGCCACAAGAUUCCUAAACUUCCCAAUUGCUCCUAUAGAUAACAUCACUAUUGUAAAACCUAAGAUUGGUGUUUGAGGUAUUUUUCUGACCCUGCAUUCUGAUGAACCAACCAGCUGGUGCCACCCAGACUGGUAAACUGGCUCAUCUGGUCUUUUGGCCCGCACCCAGGAACUGACUCAGUACAAGAAGACAAACUUCGACUCCCUAUGAUUUCAACCCAACCAAUCAGCAUUCCCUAUUCCCGACCCUGCUGCCUCCAAAUUAUCCUUGAAGAACCAUAGCCUCUGGAUUUUUGGAAAGGCAUAUUUGAGUAAUAAUAAGCUCCUGUCCUCUUGCUUAGCUGCCUCUGGGUUUAUUAAACUCUUUCUCUAUUGCAAAAACCUGCUGUUCAGUGCAUCGGCUUUGCUGGGCAGUGGGAAUGAUGAAACUGCCUGGUGAAUACAGAAGUGUUCUCUUGUCCUAUGAGUAGGUCUCAGUCUUUGAGUAAGCCUGUGCCUCUGGACUGUGAACUUCACAGUGUUUCUCAGGUUUUAUUUCCUCUUAGGUGGGACAGGGUCGCUAGACUCGGCUGGAAUUAUAUGUUUCUGUUCAUCACAUGGAAGGCUUGAGUGGGCUAGAGCUGAGAAUUUCUCUUCCCUCCAGGCCCGUUAGGCUGUGGGAAAAUCCACUGUCAGAUGAGGCUCUGGUUAGGUAGCUUCUCCUGAGGACAGGCCUUGUUAGGAAGACCCCAGUGCUCUGGCAUAUUUCAAAAUGGUUCCUUUUCCUUCUCCUCCUGCUGGAAAGGGAUUUUUCUUGGGGAAGUUUCUGCUCCAGGCCGGGUGCAGUGGCUCACACCUGUAAUCCCAGCACUUACUUUGGGAGGCCGAGGUGGGUAGAUUAUUUGAGCCCAGGAAUUCGAGGCCAGCCUGGAUAACAUAGAGAAACCCAGUCUCUCCUAAAAAUACAAAAACUAGCUGGGUGUGUGGUGCAUGCCUGUAGUCCCAGCUACUUGGGAGGCUGAGGCGAGAGGAUCCCUUGAACCUAGGAGGUCAAGGCUGCAGAGAGCCCUGAUCGUGCCACUGCACUCCAGCCUGGGUGACAGAGCCAGACCCUGUCUCAAAAAAAAAAAA